AGAGACUCCCACCCCAGCUCAGAGGGAGCAGGGGCCCAGCCAGGGACGGACCCUCAUUCCUCCCAGGGACCCCAGACCUCUGUCUCUCUCGGGUAAGUCUCCAUCUCUGUCUGUCUCUGUCUCUGUCUCUGUCUCUGUCUGUUUUUCACGCACUCAGCAAGGCCUCCUGCCCUGAGAGAGGCUCCGCCCACUACCCCCCACUUUCCCCAUAAAACCAGCUGAGUAUUUGUGCCAGGAAGACUGCGUGCAGAAGGUGACUGUCUCAGUGGAGCUGGGUCAUCUCAGGUGGGGAGUUGGGGUCCCCGAAGGUGAGGACCCUCUGGGGAGGAGGGUGCUUCUCUGAGACACUUUCUUUUCCUCACACCUGUUCCUCGCCAGCAGGCCUUGGCUCCUUGAACUUUUGGCCGCCAUGUGCUUCCCGAAGGUCCUCUCUGAUGACAUGAAGAAGCUGAAGGCCCGAAUGCACCAGGCCAUAGAAAGAUUUUAUGAUAAAAUGCAAAAUGCAGAAUCAGGACGUGGACAGGUGAUGUCGAGCCUGGCAGAGCUGGAGGACGACUUCAAAGAGGGCUACCUGGAGACAGUGGCGGCUUAUUAUGAGGAGCAGCACCCAGAGCUCACUCCUCUACUUGAAAAAGAAAGAGAUGGAUUACGGUGCCGAGGCAACAGAUCCCCUGUCCCGGAUGUUGAGGAUCCCGCAACCGAGGAGCCUGGGGAGAGCUUUUGUGACAAGGUCAUGAGAUGGUUCCAGGCCAUGCUGCAGCGGCUGCAGACCUGGUGGCACGGGGUUCUGGCCUGGGUGAAGGAGAAGGUGGUGGCCCUGGUCCAUGCAGUGCAGGCCCUCUGGAAACAGUUCCAGAGUUUCUGCUGCUCUCUGUCAGAGCUCUUCAUGUCCUCUUUCCAGUCCUACGGAGCCCCACGGGGGGACAAGGAGGAGCUGACACCCCAGAAGUGCUCUGAACCCCAAUCCUCAAAAUGAAGAUACUGACACCACCUUUGCCCUCCCCGUCACCGCGCACCCACCCUGACCCCUCCCUCAGCUGUCCUGUGCCCCGCCCUCUCCCGCACACUCAGUCCCCCUGCCUGGCGUUCCUGCCGCAGCUCUGACCUGGUGCUGUCGCCCUGGCAUCUUAAUAAAACCUGCUUAUACUUCC